ACUCCGCCCCCAGCCGGACUCUCAGGCCCCUUGCUUCUCGCGAGCGGCCGUCCGAGCACCAGCCUCGCCGCCGCAGAGACGCUCGCCACGCCGGUGCCGGAGCCGGAGCGGGGAGCCAGGCUGCGUGCGACCAGCCGCAGAGCAGAGAGCGCCCGGGGCGGGGGCCGCAGACGGACAGGGGCUCUGGGCGGCCGGGGAGCAUGCCCGCGCGGCUACGCUGAAUGGCGCCUCCUCUGCGACCCCUCGCCCGGCUGCGACCGCCGGGGAUGCUGCUCCGCGCGCUCCUGCUCCUGCUGCUGCUCAGUCCUUUGCCAGGAGUGUGGUGCUUUAGCGAACUGUCUUUUGUAAAAGAACCACAGGAUGUAACUGUCACAAGAAAGGACCCAGUCGUUUUAGAUUGCCAGGCUCACGGAGAAGUUCCUAUUAAGGUCACAUGGUUGAAAAAUGGAGCAAAAAUGUCUGAAAAUAAACGGAUCGAGGUUCUUUCUAACGGCUCUUUAUACAUCAGUGAGGUGGAAGGCAGGCGAGGAGAGCAGUCCGAUGAAGGAUUUUAUCAGUGCUUGGCAAUGAACAAAUAUGGAGCCAUUCUUAGUCAAAAAGCUCAUCUUGCCUUAUCAACUAUUUCUGCAUUUGAAGUCCAGCCAAUUUCCACUGAGGUCCACGAAGGUGGAGUUGCUCGAUUUGCAUGCAAGAUUUCAUCCCACCCUCCUGCAGUCAUAACAUGGGAGUUCAAUCGGACAACUCUACCUAUGACUAUGGACAGGAUAACUGCCCUACCAACAGGAGUAUUGCAGAUCUAUGAUGUCAGCCAAAGGGAUUCUGGAAAUUAUCGUUGUAUUGCUGCCACUGUAGCCCACCGACGUAAAAGUAUGGAGGCCUCGCUAACUGUGAUUCCAGCUAAGGAGUCAAAAUCCUUCCACACACCAACAAUUAUAGCAGGUCCACAGAACAUAACAACAUCUCUUCAUCAGACUGUAGUUUUGGAAUGCAUGGCCACAGGAAAUCCCAAACCAAUCAUUUCUUGGAGCCGCCUUGAUCACAAAUCCAUUGAUGUCUUUAAUACUCGGGUACUUGGAAAUGGUAAUCUCAUGAUAUCUGAUGUCAGGCUACAACAUGCUGGAGUAUAUGUUUGUCGGGCCACUACCCCUGGCACACGCAACUUUACAGUUGCUAUGGCAACUUUAACUGUAUUAGCUCCUCCUUCAUUUGUUGAAUGGCCAGAAAGUUUAACAAGGCCUCGAGCUGGCACUGCUCGAUUUGUGUGUCAGGCAGAAGGAAUCCCCUCUCCCAAGAUGUCAUGGUUGAAAAAUGGAAGGAAGAUACAUUCGAAUGGUAGAAUUAAAAUGUACAACAGUAAAUUGGUAAUUAACCAGAUUAUUCCUGAAGAUGAUGCUAUUUAUCAGUGCAUGGCUGAGAAUAGCCAAGGAUCUAUUUUAUCUAGAGCCAGACUGACUGUAGUGAUGUCAGAAGACAGACCCAGUGCUCCCUAUAAUGUACAUGCUGAAACCAUGUCAAGCUCAGCCAUUCUUUUAGCCUGGGAGAGGCCACUUUAUAAUUCAGACAAAGUCAUUGCCUAUUCUGUACACUACAUGAAAGCAGAAGGUUUAAAUAAUGAAGAGUAUCAAGUAGUCAUCGGAAAUGACACAACUCAUUAUAUUAUUGAUGACUUAGAGCCUGCCAGCAAUUAUACUUUCUACAUUGUAGCAUAUAUGCCAAUGGGAGCCAGCCAGAUGUCUGACCAUGUGACACAGAAUACUCUAGAGGAUGUUCCCCUGAGACCUCCUGAAAUUAGUUUGACAAGUCGAAGUCCCACUGAUAUUCUCAUCUCCUGGCUGCCAAUCCCAGCCAAAUAUCGGCGGGGCCAAGUGGUGCUGUAUCGCUUGUCUUUCCGCCUAAGUACUGAGAAUUCAAUCCAAGUUCUGGAGCUCCCGGGGACCACGCAUGAGUACCUUUUGGAAGGCCUGAAACCUGACAGUGUCUACCUGGUUCGGAUUACUGCUGCCACCAGAGUGGGGCUGGGAGAGUCAUCAGUAUGGACUUCACAUAGGACGCCCAAAGCUACAAGCGUGAAAGCCCCUAAGUCUCCAGAGUUGCAUUUGGAGCCUCUGAACUGUACCACCAUUUCUGUGAGGUGGCAGCAAGAUGUAGAGGACACAGCUGCUAUUCAGGGCUACAAGCUGUACUACAAGGAAGAAGGGCAGCAGGAGAAUGGGCCCAUUUUCUUGGAUACCAAGGACCUACUCUAUACUCUCAGUGGCUUAGACCCCAGAAGAAAAUAUCAUGUGAGACUCCUGGCUUACAACAACAUAGACGAUGGCUAUCAGGCAGAUCAGACUGUCAGCACUCCAGGAUGCGUGUCUGUUCGUGAUCGCAUGGUCCCUCCUCCACCACCACCCCACCAUCUCUAUGCGAAGGCUAACACCUCAUCUUCCAUCUUCCUGCACUGGAGGAGGCCUGCAUUCACCGCUGCACAAAUCAUUAACUACACCAUCCGCUGUAAUCCUGUUGGCCUGCAGAAUGCUUCUUUGGUUCUGUACCUUCAAACAUCAGAAACUCACAUGUUGGUUCAAGGUCUAGAACCAAACACCAAAUACGAAUUUGCCGUUCGAUUACAUGUGGAUCAGCUUUCCAGUCCUUGGAGCCCUGUAGUCUACCAUUCUACUCUUCCAGAAGCACCAGCAGGCCCACCAGUUGGAGUAAAAGUGACAUUAAUAGAGGAUGACACUGCCCUGGUUUCUUGGAAACCCCCUGAUGGCCCAGAAACAGUUGUGACCCGCUAUACUAUCUUAUAUGCAUCUAGGAAGGCCUGGAUUGCAGGAGAGUGGCAGGUCUUACACCGUGAAGGGGCAAUAACCAUGGCUUUGCUAGAAAACUUGGUAGCAGGAAAUGUGUACAUUGUCAAGAUAUCUGCAUCCAAUGAGGUGGGAGAAGGACCCUUUUCAAAUUCUGUGGAGCUGGCAGUACUUCCAAAGGAAACCUCUGAAUCAAAUCAGAGGCCCAAGCGUUUAGAUUCUGCUGAUGCCAAAGUUUAUUCAGGAUAUUACCAUCUGGACCAAAAAUCAAUGACUGGCAUUGCUGUAGGUGUUGGCAUAGCCUUGACCUGCAUCCUCAUCUGUGUUCUCAUCUUGAUAUACCGAAGUAAAGCCAGGAAAUCAUCUGCUUCCAAGACGGCACAGAAUGGAACUCAACAGUUACCUCGUACCAGUGCCUCCUUAGCUAGUGGAAAUGAGGUAGGAAAGAACCUGGAAGGAGCUGUAGGAAAUGAAGAAUCUUUAAUGCCAAUGAUCAUGCCAAACAGCUUCAUUGAUGCAAAGGGAGGAACUGACCUGAUAAUUAAUAGCUAUGGUCCUAUAAUUAAAAACAACUCUAAGAAAAAGUGGUUUUUUUUCCAAGACUCAAAGAAGAUACAAGUUGAGCAGCCUCAAAGAAGAUUUACUCCAGCGGUCUGCUUUUACCAGCCAGGCACCACUGUAUUAAUCAGUGAUGAAGACUCCCCUAGCUCCCCAGGUCAGACAACCAGCUUCUCAAGACCCUUUGGUGUUGCAGCUGAUACAGAACAUUCAGCAAAUAGUGAAGGCAGCCAUGAGACUGGGGAUUCUGGGCGGUUUUCUCAUGAGUCCAACGAUGAGAUACAUCUGUCCUCAGUUAUAAGUACCACACCCCCCAACCUCUGAUUCUUUCACUGGCAGUGAUUCAGGUGGAGAUUCCGCAUUGAGGAAGUGUGAAGACCCUGCUGUGUCAUCUGUUAGUGAGCAGACUUCCUCCUUAGUUCUGCAGCCGCCAUCUGCCAUGCUAUGCUUUGAUAAAAAUGAUUUUCCAAUCUAGACGGCCAUGCUCAGGUAUUCUCACCAUUAAAUCUGUUCGAAGGACAAUGAACAGGGAACCAAAGCCUUUUGUGAAAAUCUUAAUAUCUUUAUGGGGUAUUUUAGCUUUUUUUGAAUGUGUUUUGUUUUUUAUUUUUAAACUUGUGUAAUUUGAAUGUUUCAUUGUCAGCAAUGUGAAAGAACGGUCGAGAUGUUUGACUGGAUUAUAAAAUAUAUCACUGGAGCAAAGGGAAGACUUUUGAAAGCCCCUUUGCUGACUAUCUACCUCAGUUUGCCUCCCGGCAAACUCUGAAGACAACUUUGUUACCUCAUUUGUUGUUAUAGUUUAUCUCAGCUACAUAACCAAUGAUACUUCCUAGUAGUAUUGUGUUUUCAUUGCUGUACGUGUAAUGUGUGUGAUCAAAGGAGUCAUAUAGGUAGAUGAGUAAGAAUGUUUAUCUGAAGCUCUGAUUUUUUUAAAAAAAGAAACUAUGACAUCUGCAUGGUUUGGAUAAGUUCAUACCUCUGGCUGUGAGGACCGUUAAACCACUGAGAAGAGGAAAAGUGGGGCUAUUUCUUCUAACGAUGACCAAAACAAGAAAGUAUAUUUCUUUUGAGAACAGAACUAUUCAAUACCAGGUAGGGAUCAUUUUGCUUAAAAGGCCUUUAUGUUUUGGGCAUUAGAGUCUGAGUGCUUUAUCUCCUAUAUCCCAAACCUCAAGCUGCCCAGAACUGUGCCUUUUCUACCUUCCCCUUUGCCUGACGGUUGGCCAAAGGCUGCACUGUCUAGUUUGCAAAGCAUCCUCAACUUUGCCAGUAUUAGUUGCAAAACCCCAUGCAGAAUAUGGAUUUUUAAAGAAAAUGGGUUAAGGUGGUUUUUUUUCUUUUUUUAAAUCCCAGUUUGGCUUAAAGGAGUGAAGACAUUUCAUGAACUAUUAAGAAUGAAGGUAAAUGCAACAGUAGACAGUAAAAUGAACUCGAAGUUAUUAUGGUAACAGUGCCUUUCAGUAUAAUGAAAUUCUUUGCCUUAUACCUUUUUAAUAUUCAUGAAAUUGUUUAGGAACAGGAGUACAAAAAGUUGCCUUAAGAGUUUCUUGGAUUUUAUCAGUAACUAUUUUGAUGUAUAGUAUCUUACCAAGGCAUUUUUUUUAAGUGCAGGUUUUGUUUAGGGAUAAAUAUUCAGAGUUCUACCACCCUACUUGUGUUUUCUUGAAUUCUUUAGAGAAUAUGGUAUCUACUUAAUCUUCCUUCAGUGUCAGUGCUGUGAAUGAGGAAUGCUAACUCCAGGAGUGAGUUAAUCCUCUUGCAGGUUUGAAAUCAGCAAAUUGUUUACUCAGCUACAUAACAUAGGCCUUUUCUCCGUCAUGAGACAGUUACCUAGGUGCCGAGCAGUGGGAGAGGAUAAAGAACUAAACGCGUGUAGAGAAGGGGUCCCAUAUCCUUUUAAAAGUAUUUUUUCAAAUUUUCUGGAAGUGACUUUUGAUUCUCAUUUUAAAAGGAAUCAUAAUGGGUUUACACUUGAAAUGCUUUGUUCCUAGAGGAGGCAGGGUCAUGUUCACUGAUGUUCUAAAAUCAAAGGAAUAUUAGCAGAUAAUAGUCCCAGCAUCAUCUGCUAGUCUAAUGACUGUAGAUAUAACAUUUUUAAUUUUUUUAAAUCUGUAAUUUUGUGCCAAACUGGAUGUGAUUAAGACUAAAGUUCAAUGCCAGCAACCACUUCUGAACUAAACUCAGAGUCCCCCAGUUAGUUAUCUAAGUACGGAAUUCAUCGCAAAACAAACAAAAAAGCAGAGCUUUAGGUGAACAGUCUGCAGCAAGGAAAAAUGCUGCUCCUGCCUUUAUAGCUCCUGUUUUAUACUACCUCCUUUUAAAGUUAUUCUAGUGUUAUUUUUUUUCCUGUACUCAGGGAACGUUUUGUUACUUUUGAGCUGCCUCAUGGAAGCAUAGGCAGAUUGACAGGGUAUAGCGCUUUGUGGUUGGUAAGUAGAAGUAUAUAGGGCCAACUUUUAUCAGUAUCUAAAAUUAAGUACAGUGAGAUCAUUUUAUUUUUAAGCUUUCAUUAAAAGGCAAACAAAAUCUAAAGCUGAAACAUCAUCCAUCAUGGUUAUGGAAGAUGUGUCUAGGACUACAUGAAUUCGAGUGGUUUUAAAUGGCUAAAAAGACGAGCUAAAGUCCUUGAGGAAAGUAUUUUGUUUGUUUGGUUUUUGAUGAAUAGGCUUAUAGUUACAAUAGAACUUUAGGCUAUAACUAUUUGAUAAUUAUUUAACAGUACAUUUUUUACCUUUUCAUUUUGUUCUUAUACGGACUUUUUCAUAAUAAUUCUGUUACCAAAGAAUUUUCAGUAGAAAAUAAAAUUUUGAUUAUAAUUCCCCCCAAAUUGAAUUAACUAGAAGCAUUUAUAGAUAUGAAACUUACACAAGUAGUUACUAACCCAAAACAAUAGGGUUUAUAUUGAUUGUUGUAGUUAAAUAGAUUAGUAAUGUUAACUACCUUAUUGUUACCAGAGCAUUUAAAAUAAGUUGUAAUACUUUCUUUACCAGCAGAUCGUUCCAAAGAAUUUCAGGUAUAGUUUUUUCUUCAGCAAGUAAAUCUUCAACUAUACAGUAUUAAAGUAUUUUUAUAUUGUUGAAACUACUUGUUGGAGAGAAAAUUUUUUUUUUUUACCAAAAAUAAAUACUUUGGUCUCAUUGAAUAAGAUAUUUAGUAAUACAGCAAAGACUUCUUUUUACUUGACCAAAUCAAGCUUCUUUGAAGUCUUAAGUAUGAAAUUGUAAUUAAAAUGUGAAGAUUUUCACUCAUUUUUCAUAGUGGUAUUACUUCAUGGUAUUGUACUUCAAAGGGGCUAAUAUGCAAAUGGUAACUAUUUUCUUUUCCAAAGAUGUAUUUGCUGUAAGUACUGAUACCUGCAUGUCAUUUUUAUGCCAAAUAUUACAAGAUACUGCUCAUCAGUAUUUUCAUACCAAAGACCAUUAAGAUGUAUAGGUUAGCCUGUAAGUAAGUAAAGAUGAGCAGAUUUGAAAUAAAUUUAUUUAGAGGCCGAUAGAGAAUCUAGCUUUAGUAGCAAAAAAUAUCAAAGGGCUAAGUUUACAUAAUUAAAAGCAAUACAAUUAUAUUGGUAUUUAUCAGUGUUUUUAUUCAAGUACUUUUUAUCAGCAAAUUAAAAAGAAAAAAACCAAAGAUAUUUAAGGUUACCUCCGCAUAUAGGCAAAUAUAGUUGUACAUUAAACUGUUGUUUCUUGUUUUUAUGUUAAACCAAACAUGUCUCUUCGGAACACAGUCUGUAUACAAAUAACAUGCAUGAGGACUUUCCAUUUAAUCUGUGAUUCAGCCACAUGAUGUUUUUGCCAAAUGAUGUGAUACUUUCCAAAGCACCUUGAGUGUGAAAUGUCAACAGAAAUAUCAGCAAGCUUUUAUGUUGCAGAGUAUUAUGGUACCUCUGAAUUAGCCUGUAUAGUUCUCUUCCUGCUUUAAGCAUUACCUGGUUAGCUCAGACGGCUUGAGGCAGUCCCUUAAUAAUAGGGAUGCUUUUCAUCUCUAAGGAUGUAAGAGGCAAACAAAUCAUGUCAUUCUUUAAGUGGGCUAUGCUUUGAUAGAUGUGCUCUUUAAAGGUGUGAGAUUGGAAUUUAGAGUUGUUAAAUUGAAAUGUUUGCAUUGCACCAAAGGAGCUCAGUUUUCAAACUUUAAUGGAACCUUGGGUAAAGGGAAAAAAUUUUUAAUGAAAUCUGGGGUUUUAUAUUUUGAUUAGCCUAAAAGUAAAAAUACAGCUUUAUCCAUUAAGUGACUUUUAAAAAUCAGUUUUGCCAUACCAAAGAAAUUAGAUUCUUAGUGUCACAUGCUAUACUUUUGUCUGUGCUUGAAACGAGCAAUGCCAACAUUGGGAACAAUGACAGAGGUUUGCAUCAGUUUGUCUUGGCUUUGUUAAGGACUUCUGCCAGAAAUGUGCUCGUGGUUGACAACCCAGGAUCAUUGUUCAAGUUCUUAUGCAGACACCUUUGAAAACAAUUCAGAUCGUGUCACAAGAAUUUGGAAUUGAAAAUAUCAUUUAUUUUUUAAUGCAAGAAUACCCAGAUGUGGUUUCACUUCAGCAGUAGCUAUAGUGGUUCACUUAUAUACAUUUCUGUUUCACUGAAUGUAAAUUUUGAAUACUGAAUGUAAAAAAAAAACUCCAGUUAUAUUGAAACAGUCACUAAGACUGCACAUGUGUUUUGCAGACUUUCUUCCUGACCAUUUGCCACAUGGGUCUCUGAUAAGAUUCUGUUGGUUUAAUAGUCAAAAUAAUCUUUGCAGUUUGUGAGCACUGAGUAGCAGGUUCUGGAGACUACCAUAUACAACCAGUUGUCUAAUUGUGAUUUUUUUAUUGAUGUUUAGAAGAAUGUAACCGUAGAGUUCUGUGUUAAGUUGAUUUAUGCUCAGGACAUAAGAUCACAGGCUAAUGCAAUGUGUAUGUUUCAGGCUUUAAUCUUCUCAAUUUCCCUUUUUAAGCCGUUGAUGGUGUUUAAGAUUAACAUGACAGUCUUGUAUUUUUACCAGAUACUGUAUUAUUUUUCCUAUUGCUGCUGUAACACAUUACCAUGAAGGUGGUGGCUUAAAAUAACACAAAUUUUUCUUAAGUUCUGCAGAUCAGAAGUCUAACACAGGUCUCCCUGGGACAAAAUCAAGGCGCUUGCAGGGCUGUUUCUUUUUGAGGCUUUAGGGAAAAAUCUAUUUCCUUUUCUAGUUUUUUAAGGCUGGGAACCCCUCCUUCCAUCUUCAAAGCCAGCCAUGUAGCAUCUCUCUGAAGCUCCUUCCGUUAUCAUUUCUCUUUGUCCAACCCCAGCUGAUACAGGUUAUCUAGGUUUAAGGAUUCCAGUGAUCACAUUGAGCCCACCUAAAUAAUCCAGGAUAAUCUCCCCAACUGAAGUUCCUCAACUUAAUCACAUCUACAGAGUUCCUUUUGCUAUGUUUGGUAACAUAUUCACUGGUUCCAGGGAUUUGGGCAUGGACUUCUGUAGGUGGCCAGUAUUUUGCCCACAACAGGUACAUUCUUUCUGUGGAAUUCUGAUCCCUGUAAAAUGUCUGUAGCAUUAAAGAGAUUGGAAAUCUGAGGUCAUGUGCCCCUUGGGGAUCUUUAAAGAUUAAAAGCAUGAAAACUUUGACUUGUAGCCUACCAAAAUUAUACACUAAACUUUCUCUCCAAAAUACUUGUGAAACAAUUUAUCUUUAAAGUUUCUGAAUAUGUGCUUCAUAAAAUAACAUCUCAUGUUUAUCAGCAAGUGUCCUAAAUAUUUGCGUCUAACUUUAUGGAAUUUAUUCAGAAAAAGAAUUGAAAACUCUUCUUAUAGUUACCCUUUCUCCUUUUCUCUUCAGUGGUUAUGUUGCUGGGGAAGAGUUGGGGGAAGACCUCAAAACACAGGAACUCAGAGUGAUGAACAGGACCAUGCUCAAGUUUAUUCUUUGUUUUCUUUUAAUGACAUAUUCACAACAUUCACAACUUUCUGCCUUUAAAUCUGGUUCCUCUCUUCAGCUUCACCAAGCCACUGAAUGCUUUUCAGUUUUAUUAACCCUCACAUUCCCCAUCCUUCUCAGCAAGAGCCUCUCCUUAUGCCAUCAGCAUGUAUAUACAUUUCCUAGGAAAUUUGAUCUUUCUUGUCAUUCUUUUUUGGUUCCAAUCGGCCUUUUCCUGGUUCUCAAAGCUCUAGUUUCUUCUAAUUUCUGGAUCAUCGCAAGUCUGGCCCUCUUUGAACUUUAAAACAUAAUGUCUAAUUCCACCCCAAUUUUCAGCAUUUCUUCAACUAAAUCGAUAAAGCUGUCUCCAUUAUGAGAAAGGCCAGAAUAAUACUCCGAGUAAGCAUAAGAAAGCUGGUCAUUUUACAACUUCUCCCGACUCUAGGAAGUAAUAUGAUGCCAUUUGUUGAGCAUCUACAGUGUGCCAAGCACAUGGUUCAUCUCUGCAAACUGCUGCUACAUUCUGUAAAGCAAGUAUUAUCCGCAUUUUAGGGAUUAGGAACAGCUUCCUGAUCUCUUGCCAAAAGUCACAGCUAGUGAGUGGUUUAGGCAAGAUACAAACCCUAGUUAGUUAAUCCUUACUCAGAAGUGUAUAGGACUAUGAUACAUUGUCUCAGCUUAAAAAAAAAAAAAAAAAAAAAAGGUAUUUAAUCACCCAGGGUCAUAGUGCCUUCCAUAGUGUGACCAGAUACAACUGUUUUUUCCUUGUAUCCACAAAAGCCAGGUUGUGUCAGAACAACCUUUCUACAGAGUAAUAACCAAUCGAAAAAGAGAAGACUACCUUAUUUAAAUCCACUUAUUCACAGGAGGGAUUAAGGCGGCUGUAACUCAUCCCUUAUCAUCUCCUAAUUUCUCUCCUCCAAAACCUUCCAUUUAUCUCAGCUAAAAUUGUGUCUGAAGGCUGUUUGUACUUAGAGUUACAUUACAAAUAAGGUAGGCAUGGUUUCUAGAGUCCUUUUCUAGUCAAGCAUUUCCUUAUUCGACAAUGUCUUCAGAAUUGCAUUUUAUCUUUUGUAAUUUUCUGUAGCUCCCAUAUUCCAAACAGGAAUUCAUUGACUUGAAAAAGUCAGGUGUGUAAACAGUAAUCCUUUCUUGUUAGGUCUGAAGAGUUCAUGAUUUUUUAUGAAUAUAAACUAAUUUAUUAUUUGCAUUAAUGUAGGAGACAGCAAAGUUAACGGAGAGUCAUAAAACAGAACAAGUAUAAGUUAGGCUUUGGAGCACCUAAGUUCUAAUCUUGACAAUUUUGAGAAUCGUUUGGUACAAAAAUUCUUAAACUGUUUCUGUGCCUUCUCCAUCCAUGAAAUGAGGAUAAUUUUUUUGUGCAAAAUGAAACAAUAGUACUUUGAAAACUUAAGAGAAAAUUCAAGUGUAAAUAAUCAUAAUCUGAAACUCAUUUGUAUGAGGCUGUGAAAGAUUUUACAGACUCUUUCUUUUCAAGUCAGCCUUUGCAAUUAUAUUUUGCCUUUGUUGAAAUGAAAAAUGUUUGCAUCUCCCGUACGCAUACACAAAACCAAUAGAAGAAAGUGGUUGGUAAAAGAUAUAGCUGAAAUGGAAACACUCAUAUGUUAGGUGGAUAAAAUCAUAAGAGAAAAUGGGAAUUGACUGUACUUUCAAAGUACUAAAUUUGAAGUCAUCUUACUCCAAUUUAAGUCAUAUAUAUAUAUAUAUAUAUAUAUAUAUAUAUAUAUAUAUAUAUAUAUAUAUUGGCUUUUAAAGAGUUAAAGAGAGAAUCAGAUCUGUCCAGCAGGAUAGAUGGGUGAGGAGAAAAGUACAUAUUUAGGAUUUUUCUCUAAAAGAUCUUUUUCAAGAUUAUGGAGUAUUUUAAUAUUUCUGCAAACUAUUCCAAAUGAAUGCAUUUUAUAUAGGGCAACACAUACUGGCACCUGAUUCUGGUUUAUUCGAGUUCAUAUGUAGGGUUUGUUGGGAAGAAUUAUAUGAUUGGCUUCUUUUUUUAGAGGAAAUAUUUUCCCUUUUUUCUUAUCCAUAUACUAUUCUGAACAGCUUUGCAGAUUUCCUUAAGUUCAUAGCUUGUAAGUAGUUCAUGGUAUAUAGACAUAGUCUUGACUUACAACUGAAAAAAAAUUUAUGUUACAGAAGUUUAUUUUUUCUAUGGAACUGUCUUUAAAAACAAAAAUAUUACAAAUCUUGACCUUGAAAUAUUCUGUUUCCUGUUAUCACAUUCUGGAUAUCUAUUUUGUUUGCAAAUGAAAAUUAUUACUGAUGAUUAGCAACUUGAGCCUGUUAAUAGGAAAUUGCAAAGCCUGAAUACACACACAUUGCCUUAGCCUAUCAGUAGAGUAGAGGACAUAUGUUAAGAAAAUGUGUCUGCUUGUUGCUGUUGUUGGACAAAAUUUUAUGUCUGUGUGUAUGAUUUUUUUUUUUCUAUUUUCUUCAAAGAUGUGAAUUAAAUGAAAGUGUGGGAGCCAGUUAAAUUAUUUUGUAUUAUGGGUGUUCUGGAUCCUUUCACUCCGUAUACCAUUUUCUUGUAAGGGCAGCAUUUGUAGACUUGCUAAUGGACUGUAGAGCUGAGCUAUAUUAAUUUUAUACUUGACUCAGGGGAUCAGUUCUGUGAAUGCCAUUGCACGAAGAAAGCAAAUGUUUGCCUUGAUUUUGAAUGUAUCUUUUUAAUGUCUUCUUAAAACAUAUUUGUUUAAUAAUGUAGAUUUGUUUUUUUUUUUCUAGUAUCAUAGUAAAUAUUGCUUAGUACUUGCCCCCACCCCACUGGGUAGUUUAUAUACUACCCUAUAGGUCAUGCCAAAAAUGAAUAAAAGUUUAAAUGCCAAAAUGUUUAUGAAACUGCUGUCUAAAUACUGAUUGAUUGCACAAUUUAAAUAAAAGCUUUCCUUAGUUAAAAAAGA